CCCCGAGCCGCCUGGCACCUCCGCCGCUUCUCCCCUGGACGCCCCUCCGCCCCACUGGGUCCUCCAGCUCCAGGCUGGACUCCUAAAGCCGCAGUGCCCCGUGCCUGUUUCCUCAUUUGGUGACACACGCAGUGCAUGCAAGAAGUUGGAGUGUUACCGGAAAAGGGCUUGAACCCGUAUAAGGCUGAGAAGAAGAUUCACUCUUUUGAGCGUGCAGAACAAACUGGAGGGAAAAAAAAAUGAGAUUUAACUUUAUCAGAGGAUUCAGAGGAUAUCUCUGAGGACGCAGAAAGUUAAUCCGCAUGAUCACCUCGUGAUUAUUUUCUGAGGGGAAAAUGCCUAAAAAAAAGACUGGUGCGAGGAAGAAGGCUGAGAACCGCCGAGAACGUGAAAAACAACUAAGAGCAUCAAGAAGCACUAUAGAUUUAGCUAAACAUCCAUGUAAUGCCUCAAUGGAAUGUGACAAGUGUCAGAGGCGGCAGAAGAAUAGAGCAUUUUGCUACUUUUGUAAUUCUGUACAGAAGUUACCAAUUUGUGCACAGUGUGGGAAAACAAAGUGCAUGAUGAAGUCUUCAGACUGUGUCAUAAAGCAUGCUGGUGUAUACAGUACUGGCCUUGCAAUGGUGGGUGCAAUAUGUGACUUCUGUGAAGCUUGGGUUUGCCAUGGUAGGAAAUGUCUCAGUACACAUGCUUGUGCCUGCCCUCUUACCGAUGCUGAGUGUGUUGAAUGUGAACGAGGCGUGUGGGACCAUGGAGGCAGAAUAUUCAGUUGUUCUUUUUGCCAUAACUUUCUCUGUGAAGAUGAUCAAUUUGAGCAUCAAGCCAGCUGCCAGGUUUUAGAGGCAGAAACAUUUAAAUGUGUUUCAUGCAAUCGGCUUGGUCAGCACUCAUGUCUCCGUUGUAAGGCUUGUUUCUGUGAUGAUCAUACAAGGAGCAAAGUGUUUAAGCAAGAAAAAGGAAAACAGCCUCCUUGUCCUAAAUGUGGGCAUGAAACUCAGGAGACUAAGGACCUUAGCAUGUCAACACGCUCCCUGAAAUUUGGCAGGCAGACUGGAGGUGAAGAGGGAGAUGGAGCUUCUGGGUAUGAUGCUUAUUGGAAGAACCUUUCAUCUGAUAAGUAUGGUGAUACCAGCUACCACGAUGAGGAGGAGGAUGAGUAUGAAGCAGAGGAUGAUGAAGAGGAAGAAGAUGAAGGCAGAAAGGAUUCAGAUACUGAGUCAUCAGAUUUGUUUACUAAUUUGAAUUUAGGAAGGACCUAUGCUAGUGGCUAUGCUCACUAUGAGGAACAAGAGAACUAGGGGAGCUGCUCUGGUGGCCGUGUGUGAGAGGAGCAGGAGUGAGUGUGUGUGCUUGAUGAAUUGUGUGUGGUUGUUCAAAAGUACCUUAGCCACUUAGCCUUGUGCAGAAGACUAGUUACACUUAAUGGGCCAAGCAAUAGGGUGUAGCGUUUUUAUAGAACUGAUAAUCAGGCUUAUGGCAUAAGAAAAAUGAGUUUCAAAUUUAAGAUGUUUAUUGAUCGAAGCAAUUGAAGUAUCAUGGAUUGGAUUGUUACUGAUUUCAGUAAAGUAUGUUUUGCCAAUUAGAUACAUAUAUACAAGAUAAAGGAAUAGGAUGGUAAUAUAUUUGUUUGAAAUUAAAUUACUGUUUUUAUUAAAAAAUACUGCUUCAUUGGGCUGAUUUUGUAAAAUGUAAUGAGUAAAAUGAAUUACUGUAUUUUUCCUUUUAUGUCCACAGAAUGAGAGUCAUAUGUUGUUAUAUUCUAAAUUUUCAUUAAAUAUUCAUGUCACCUUGAGUUGUCAUGAUAAGUAUGUUUUAGUAUUUGACUUAUUCUUCUCUUUCUUCACAAUGUAUGUCCUCAGUGGUACCUAUUAUUGAUGCCUUAAAUGUAUUGAUAAGGUGACUAGUUAGCCAUUUUUCAGAGAUACAGUAUCAGAAAUAGUAUUAUUACAGAAGCUUUACCCAGGACAUUUUAUUUCUCUUUGAAUAAAUCUAUUAUUUCACUUAAA